CAACGAUGUGAAGGUUAUAAGCUGCACUGCAUGGUUGCUGCUGGAUGUGUUGUGUUCCUGGCUUCCCUCUGGAUGCUGACAGAAACAAGGGAAUUUCUGCUGAAGUGACAAGGCAAGCCAGAGCCAAAGCAGGUUGGACCCAGCUUGUCCCCACAGAGACGUGUGCUUCCCUCUCUCUCUGAGAGCGACCUGUUAACCGCAAAUACCUGGAAGGUCUGGGACAUGGAGAACGACCCCUCGAGACGAAGAGAGUCCAUCUCUCUCACACCUGUGGCCAAGGGUCUGGAGAACAUGGGGGCUGAUUUCUUGGAAAGCCUGGAGGAAGGCCAGCUCCCUAGGAGUGACUUGAGCCCCGCAGAGAUCAGGAGCAGCUGGAGCGAGGCGGCGCCGAAGCCCUUCUCCAGAUGGAGGAACCUGCAGCCAGCCCUGAGAGCCAGAAGCUUCUGCAGGGAGCACAUGCAGCUGUUUCGAUGGAUCGGCACAGGCCUGCUCUGCACUGGGCUCUCUGCCUUCCUGCUGGUGGCCUGCCUCCUGGAUUUCCAGAGGGCCCUGGCUCUGUUUGUCCUCACCUGUGUGGUCCUCACCUUCCUGGGCCACCGCCUGCUGAAACGGCUUCUGGGGCCAAAGCUGAGGAGGUUUCUCAAGCCUCAGGGCCAUCCCCGCCUGCUGCUCUGGUUUAAGAGGGGUCUAGCUCUUGCUGCUUUCCUGGGCCUGGUCCUGUGGCUGUCUCUGGACACCUCCCAGCGGCCUGAGCAACUGGUGUCCUUCGCAGGAAUCUGCGUGUUCGUCGCUCUCCUCUUUGCCUGCUCAAAGCAUCAUUGCGCAGUGUCCUGGAGGGCCGUGUCUUGGGGACUUGGACUGCAGUUUGUACUUGGACUCCUCGUCAUCAGAACAGAACCAGGAUUCAUUGCGUUCGAGUGGCUGGGCGAGCAGAUCCGGAUCUUCCUGAGCUACACGAAGGCUGGCUCCAGCUUCGUGUUUGGGGAGGCGCUGGUCAAGGAUGUCUUUGCCUUUCAGGUUCUGCCCAUCAUUGUCUUUUUCAGCUGUGUCAUAUCCGUUCUCUACCACGUGGGCCUCAUGCAGUGGGUGAUCCUGAAGAUUGCCUGGCUGAUGCAAGUCACCAUGGGCACCACAGCCACUGAGACCCUGAGUGUGGCUGGAAACAUCUUUGUGAGCCAGACCGAGGCUCCAUUACUGAUCCGGCCCUACUUGGCAGACAUGACACUCUCUGAAGUCCACGUUGUCAUGACCGGAGGUUACGCCACCAUUGCUGGCAGCCUGCUGGGUGCCUACAUCUCCUUUGGGAUCGAUGCCACCUCGUUGAUUGCAGCCUCUGUGAUGGCUGCCCCUUGUGCCUUGGCCCUCUCCAAGCUGGUCUACCCGGAGGUGGAGGAGUCCAAGUUUAGGAGGGAGGAAGGAGUGAAACUGACCUAUGGAGAUGCUCAGAACCUCAUAGAAGCAGCCAGCACUGGGGCCGCCAUCUCCGUGAAGGUGGUCGCCAACAUCGCUGCCAACCUGAUUGCGUUCCUGGCUGUGCUGGACUUUAUCAAUGCUGCCCUCUCCUGGCUGGGAGACAUGGUGGACAUCCAAGGGCUCAGCUUCCAGCUCAUCUGCUCCUACAUCCUGCGGCCUGUAGCCUUCUUGAUGGGUGUGGCGUGGGAGGACUGCCCAGUGGUAGCUGAGCUGCUGGGGAUCAAGCUGUUUCUGAACGAGUUUGUGGCCUAUCAAGACCUCUCCAAGUACAAGCAACGCCGCCUGGCAGGGGCCGAGGAGUGGGUCGGCGACAGGAAGCAGUGGAUCUCCGUCAGAGCUGAAGUCCUCACGACGUUUGCCCUCUGUGGAUUUGCCAAUUUCAGCUCCAUUGGGAUCAUGCUGGGAGGCUUGACCUCCAUGGUCCCCCAACGGAAGAGCGACUUCUCCCAGAUAGUGCUCCGGGCGCUCUUCACGGGAGCCUGUGUGUCCCUGGUGAACGCCUGUAUGGCAGGGAUCCUCUACAUGCCCAGGGGGGCUGAAGUUGACUGCAUGUCCCUCUUGAACACGACCCUCAGCAGCAGUAGCUUUGAGAUUUACCAGUGCUGCCGUGAGGCCUUCCAGAGCGUCAAUCCAGAGUUCAGCCCAGAGGCCCUGGACAACUGCUGUCGGUUUUACAACCACACGAUCUGUGCACAGUGAGGACAGAACAUGCUUGUGCUUCUGCGCUUCUGAGGGCUGUUCUCCCCCGGGAACCAUCUGUCCCCACCUUCCCUUUCCCAGAGCCCUCUUCAGGGAAGCCACAGGACUUAGACCCAGCUCAAUCCCACAAUUGGGAAGGGUUCAUGGAGUGAGUGUGCAGAGAGUGAGUGAGGACAUAAGGAAGGACAUGUCCCACUCCAUCCCCCUUCCUGCUCCCCCAUUUCCUAACUCCCCCAGUGUGAAUUCUCAGGGUCACUUCUGCCUCCUCCCGUUUCCCCUCCACAUCCAAACAGCACCCUGGUCCUCUCUAUCCCCCCUCUCCUGGGGUCCCUCACAUGCCCCUUCCCUUCUGUUGUGGGCUGCACACCAAAGCCUCCUCCCCUCCCCACUUCCUAGGCACUAGGAUCUCUCUGUGGCUUCCCCUGCUGGGUGGUGUCACCUCUUUCUCUGCUUUCAGAGAAACCCUUCCCGCCUUUCCUCAGAGUGCUUCCCAAACUGAGGUCCCAUGGCACACUGUCCUGGGAGGCGUUCAGAGGGUUCCAUGAUGGACUAGGUUUGGAACCACUGGGUUAAAUAAACUUAGAGAGGGCUGUUUAGA